CUCGCGGACCCCGGAAGCGCGCGUGGCCGCCAUGGCGCGGAAUGUGGUGUACCCCCUGUACCGGCUGGGUGGCCCACAACUUCGGGUGUUCCGAACCAACUUCUUCAUUCAGCUGGUGCGGCCCGGUGUGGCCCAGCCCGAGGACACCGUGCAGUUCCGGAUCCCCAUGGAAAUGACAAGGGUGGACCUCAGGAAUUACCUCGAGGGCAUCUAUAACGUGCCCGUGGCUGCUGUGCGGACACGGGUGCAGCAUGGCUCUAACAAGAGAAGAGAUCACAGAAACGUGAGGAUCAAGAAGCCGGACUACAAGGUCGCCUACGUGCAGCUGCCCUCCCAGACACCCAGCAAGGAGCAAAAUGGCCAGGGCAGCACCCUCUGUUUCCGGAGCAGCUGCAGCAAGGGGUGGUCAACCUGGGGGACCAGGGACCCCAGACCCGCUUGGAGUCCUGUGGGUGGCCGCAUUCCCAGGAAGGCUGGAUCCGGAGGACCGGCCAACAGGAUCGCUCAGGAUGGACGUCUUCUACUCAACAGCUUCAGGAGUGCCGAGCCACAAGGCUGCAGGAGCCUGGGUCCCCAGUCGCCUGGAGGAGACCCUGCCCACACCAUACUCAGACCACCCUCCCAGAAUGGUGACUGUGCAGAGAUGCACGCAUGUCGGCUGCACCCCGCCAUCUUGGGGGUACAUAUUUCCAGAAAGAAAUCACUUCCAAUUCCAAGGGCUCCAUGGAGGCGGAUUUUUCCAUCUGGGCUUUUCUGAUGAGUUUUCUUGGAGGAAACUUCUGCGUUAACUCACUUCCCUCCUCUGUGCCUCAUGCGGGGACAAUUAGGGGAGGCAGGGAGACCUGAAGCCCGGAGCCGGCCGCCGGGAACCCGUUUGUCCGUGCGCGCUCGGAAACCUGGAGGCAGCUCCCCAGUUCCUGUCUCUUCCCCGGGCGGGUCCCCACCUGGCCUGUGGCGUGACUGUGAGUCAGGGGUCUGGAUCCUCCGAGGCCCGCAGGAUCCGGGUGGAUGGGCCACGUCUCUGCACGUGCAGCCUCUCCUGGGUCCCCUCUCACAUCCGGCUCUGGCUGGGCCAUUUCCCACGCUGUGGCUUCCAACCGCUCAGCCCGACUGCAUCUGCACCGUUGCUGGCCGAGGGGAGGCUGCCUCUGCCUUCCCAGCCAGGACCCUGGGCCCCCUGUGUGUUUCUGGACCUCACUCUUGGCGGCCACCCGCGCCCUCACCCACAUUCUCCCUCCGUGGCCUCGUGGCCUGGUACACUUGGGCUCUGGGCUGCUGUUUCCAGGACCCAUGGGACAGGUGGCCUGGCUGCCCAGAGCCACGCUCCCCGGGCCCUUCUCCCCUCCUGCCCUUCUUCCCAGCAACCUGCAGAUGGUUGGUGUUCCCUUCACCUGUGCCUGCCUGGCCUUCUCCUGGCCCCACGGUGAGGCUUCUGGGAGCACGAACUGCUAAGGGCUGCACUGUGUCUCUGCCCAGGCACGGAAGUCCUGACCCCACAACCUCAGAAUGGGCCUGUCUAGAGGUGGAUCUUUAAGGAGGUACCAAGUUAAGAUGGAAUCAUUAGGAUGACCCUGAGCCCAUCCAACUGGUGUUUCUAUAAGCGGAGAUCAGAGCACAGACGCUGACAGGGCAACAGCCACGUGAGGACACAGGGAGAUGGCGGGGUCUGCAAGCCCAGGAAAGAGGCCUCAGGAGGAACCCGCCCCGCGGCACCUUGACCUCGGACUCUCUCUCUCACGCUGUGGUACUUUCUGACAGCAGUCCAAGAAGACUGAACUCGUCACCUCCCGCUCCGUUUCCCACCACCUCUGGCCUGCCUGGCCUGUUUCCUCCAGCCUCCCACCCCUCCUUGUCAGCCAGUUGAAAAUGCCCCUUUUCCCAGGACUGGUCUCUCCAUGGGCACCCCUGACCUCCAUAGGGAGUCCCACUGUGCCUCGCUUUGGGGGUAAUCAAGAUUGCCCCUCAGCCUCUCAGGCCCCUCCCUGCUCUUGGGUGCUGGAUGCCCUGGGGACCCUUCACCAAGUCGCCCUGCUGUGGCUCUAGCUGGGCAUGAACAGGUGCUGUCUCCAGAGCCCGAGGUCCUCAGAGGGGCCAGGCCCUCUGUCGUGGGAACAAGGACCCUAAGGCCCGGGAGGGGAGCGGCACACGGAGAACAGGCUGGGGACCUGGGCGUGAGCAGCUGGGCAUGAGCCCUGCCCGCUUUGUCCCCUGGGGAGCCUGGCCUGGGAAGCAUUAGCUUGGCCAGAGUCUCCCUGAUGGGAUUGGAAGCCCAGCCCUGCCUGGGAAGGCGCCUGUGGGCUGAUGGGGAUGGGGUGGCCGGGGCCCUGGGCUUCCAGGAUGCGUGAAGCUCCUGCCCACACAGGGAGUCAGGUUCCUGUCCUGUGCACCUGGAUGCUCCGGGAAGGACUGCCUUGGGGUCUGGCCACGAACUCCACUGGCUCCAGCUGUGCAGCCCCGCAGAAGGUGCUGCAGCACCCGCCCUGCCCAACACAGGCGCGGCUCUGGGGUCCGGCGUGGGCAGGGGAUCUGGCAUGGACCCAUCCUCUUGAGGGCCUCUGGCGUGGUGGGUGGCAGGCUGGGGAGAGGGCUGCUGCCCUCCUUCUGGGCCUCCCAGCCCUGCAAGGGUGGCCUGGAAGGCGGGCAGUGCACUCUGGCCUGAGGGCCCGUGGGAGCCAGUCCUCUUUAGAAGGGCCCCCUCCAUCCCCACCCAUCAGCAUUCAUGGCCCUAGUACCAGGGAAGGAGGCCCAGGCCAUGGGACCCCUGGACCAACCAACCCAGCCAGUUCUGGAGCUACCCGGGGCACCCGAAGAGUACGUCCCUCUGUUCCCAGGAGCCCCACUUUAGGGCCGUUUCCUGGGCUGACUCCCUGGCCUGCAAGCCCCCAGGUUGCUUACUAAGCCCAAACCCCCACCCAUGCCACUGACCGCCCCUGCUCUCUGUUAUCCAAAGCCCUCAGCUCCCUGUGCCCUCUGGGACACGGGGCCUCCUCCCUACAAGGAAAGCUGGGUCCCAAGCGCGACCCUGGCCUCUCCAUCCUGCCCCCUGGCCACCCACCCCCUCGCCCUGUUUCUCUGUCCUGCAGGACUUCCUCUGGCUUUAUUGUUUUAAGUUGGUGGUUGGGCCAACAGCCAGCUUCAAUUACACUCCUCGCCUCCUCCUCCUCCUCCUCCUCCUCCUCCUCCUCCUCCUCCACCUCUUCCAGCCCUUCUCUGCCCUAGGCCCAGGGGUGGGCCUUGGGCUACAGCUGACUGUGGUACCCAGGCAAAACAGCCCUAGGAAAAUGAUAACAGAAAAUAAUAAAAAUUAUUUUUCUCUC